GAGGAGCCUGAGGAAGAGGGCGGCGACGGUGGUGGUGACUGAGCGGAGCCCGGUGACAGGAUGGGAAAGGGAAUAAACCACCCUCCUCGCUCCUGAAAUAACAUCUAGCUGCCAUUGAGAUGAGCAGGUGUGCUCUCAGAGGGCGGGAUUUGGCGCUUGCAAUUGCUGGAACUGUUUCUUUCCACGGGUUGCUACGCCUCUUUAGGGCUGGGCACAGAUUGGUGUUGGUAUUAGGAGAUCUGCACAUCCCACACCGGUGCAACAGUUUGCCAGCUAAAUUCAAAAAACUCCUGGUGCCAGGAAAAAUUCAGCACAUUCUCUGCACAGGAAACCUUUGCACCAAAGAGAGUUAUGACUAUCUCAAGACUCUGGCUGGUGAUGUUCAUAUUGUGAGAGGAGACUUCGAUGAGAAUCUGAAUUAUCCAGAACAGAAAGUUGUGACUGUUGGACAGUUCAAAAUUGGUCUGAUCCAUGGACAUCAAGUUAUUCCAUGGGGAGAUAUGGCCAGCUUAGCCCUGUUGCAGAGGCAAUUUGAUGUGGACAUUCUUAUCUCGGGACACACACACAAAUUUGAAGCAUUUGAGCAUGAAAAUAAAUUCUACAUUAAUCCAGGUUCUGCCACUGGGGCAUAUAAUGCCUUGGAAACAAACAUUAUUCCAUCAUUUGUGUUGAUGGAUAUCCAGGCUUCUACAGUGGUCACCUAUGUGUAUCAGCUAAUUGGAGAUGAUGUGAAAGUAGAACGAAUCGAAUACAAAAAACCUUAAAGCCAGGCCUGUCUUGAUGAUUUUUGGUUUUUUUUCAUUGUCCUGUUGAAAUCAAGUAAUUAAACAUUUAAGAGCCACAAAAUUGUAUCACUUUUAUAAUAUUUUGCAGUAAAAUAUAAUACCAUCUUCUCUGUUAAUACAUAAUUGCUCCAAGCUUCCUGUAAACUAUAAGAAUAUAUUUAGUUUACAGUAUAUGGAUUCUAUGAAAAAAUGUCCACAACACAGUAAUUGGUCACUUGUUAAGAAAAAUUUAUCCUUGUAAGUAUCUUCAAAGUUGAUAUUUGGAACUUUAUUCCAAAAGUAGUGCAUGUGGAGAAAGAAUCUAGACUUUCUUGUAUACAUUUUUCUCUUCUCCAGUAAUAAACAAUUACCUUUCAUUUAUACUUUGAUAACCUGUAUUUAAUUUAAAAAAAAACAUAAAAAUGAGGAACCAAGUGAAACUACGGAUAUAAAUAUUAAAGUGGACGAGAUGACCUUUCAGAGCUCUUCUCUUACAUUGUGUCAUAAUGUUGGACUCAGAUUUUAUUUGCUAAAUAAUAUACCAUGCCGACAUUAACAGUGAUUCUUCAAACUGUUGCUAUUUCCAUUUUUCAAGGUUUAAUAAAAGUUUUAAAAAUACAAGUUUAGGGGCCGGGCACAGUGGCUCACACCCUAAUCCCAACACUUUGGGAGGCUGAGGCAGGUGGAUCACCUGAGGUCAGGAGUUCAAGACCAGCCUGGCCAACAUGGUGAAACCCUGUCUGUACUAAAAAUACAAAAUUAGCCAGCAUGGUGCUACAUGCCUGUAUUCCCAGCUACUCGGGAGGCUGAGGCAGUAGAAUCACUUGAAUCCUGGAGUUGGAGGUUGCAGUGAGCCGAGAUCACACCAUUGCACUCCAGCCUGGUCAACAAGAGCAUAACUCCGUCUCAAAAAAAAACAAAA